CGAUCACUCACUCACUCCCUCACUCACUCCCACACUCACUCACUCACGUCUCCCCCAGCUCACCUCCUCCCCACCCCAGCAUGGCCACGUCUACCAUGUCCGUCUGCUCCAGCGCUUACUCUGACUCCUGGCAGGUGGACGCCUGCCCAGAGAGCUGCUGUGAGCCCCCCUGCUGCGCCACCAGCUGCUGCGCCCCGGCCCCCUGCCUGACCCUGGUCUGCACCCCAGUGAGCUGUGUGUCCAGCCCCUGCUGCCAGGCGGCCUGUGAGCCCAGCCCCUGCCAGUCAGGCUGCACCAGCUCCUGCACGCCCUCGUGCUGCCAGCAGUCUAGCUGCCAGCCAGCUUGCUGCACAUCCUCCCCCUGCCAGCAGGCCUGCUGCGUGCCUGUCUGCUGCAAGCCAGUCUGCUGUGUGCCCGUCUGCUGCAAGCCUGUCUGCUGCAAGCCCAUCUGCUGUGUGCCCGUCUGCUCUGGGGCUUCCUCUUCAUGCUGCCAGCAGUCUAGCCGCCAGCCGGCUUGCUGCACCACCUCCUGCUGCAGACCCUCCUCCUCCGUGUCCCUCCUCUGCCGCCCCGUGUGCAGGUCCACCUGCUGUGUGCCCAUCCCCUCCUGCUGUGCCCCUGCCUCCACCUGCCAGCCCAGCUGCUGCCGCCCGGCCUCCUGCGUGUCCCUCCUCUGCCGCCCCACGUGCUCCCGCCUCUCUUCCGCGUGCUGCGGCCUCUCCUCAGGCCAGAAGUCCAGCUGCUGACGGGCAGGUCCCGUUUCUCCAGAGUUGUUCCAGGGCCAUCUCUGACUUCCGAAAAUCCUUGCAGCCCUGAGCCCUGUCUGAGUCUCCUCUGCCCAUAGCCACUGCACCUCCAGCCAGCAAUGCUGAGCUUUCAUGCCGAUUCCCUCCAGGCAUGCAUCUCUCCCACACCCUCAUCUCCAUGCUGGCCAGCCGGUGGUCACUGUGUCCUGCCCCAUGUGAGUGAUCAGUCUGUCAACAAAUAAAGUCACCAAUGUGCCCUC